CGCCAUGGCGGCGCCGGGUUGCGGACCCUGAGCGCCGGCGCGGGGCGCGCACCAUGAACUCGUGGGACGCGGGCCUGGCGGGGCUACUGGUGGGCACGAUGGGCGUCUCGCUGCUGUCCAACGCGCUGGUGCUGCUCUGCCUGCUGCACAGCGCGGACAUCCGCCGCCAGGCGCCGGCGCUCUUCACCCUGAACCUCACGUGCGGGAACCUGCUGUGCACCGUGGUCAACAUGCCGCUCACGCUGGCCGGCGUCGUGGCGCAGCGGCAGCCGGCGGGCGACCGCCUGUGCCGCCUGGCUGCCUUCCUCGACACCUUCCUGGCUGCCAACUCCAUGCUCAGCAUGGCCGCGCUCAGCAUCGACCGCUGGGUGGCCGUGGUCUUCCCGCUGAGCUACCGGGCCAAGAUGCGCCUCCGCGACGCGGCGCUCAUGGUGGCCUACACGUGGCUGCACGCGCUCACCUUCCCAGCCGCCGCGCUCGCCCUGUCCUGGCUCGGCUUCCACCAGCUGUACGCCUCGUGCACGCUGUGCAGCCGGCGGCCAGACGAGCGCCUGCGCUUCGCCGUCUUCACUGGCGCCUUCCACGCUCUCAGCUUCCUGCUCUCCUUCGUCGUGCUCUGCUGCACGUACCUCAAGGUGCUCAAGGUGGCCCGCUUCCAUUGCAAGCGCAUCGACGUGAUCACCAUGCAGACGCUGGUGCUGCUGGUGGACCUGCACCCCAGUGUGCGGGAACGCUGUCUGGAGGAGCAGAAGCGGAGGCGACAGCGAGCCACCAAGAAGAUCAGCACCUUCAUAGGGACCUUCCUUGUGUGCUUCGCGCCCUAUGUGAUCACCAGGCUAGUGGAGCUCUUCUCCACGGUGCCCAUCGGCUCCCACUGGGGGGUGCUGUCCAAGUGCUUGGCGUACAGCAAGGCCGCAUCCGACCCCUUUGUGUACUCCUUACUGCGACACCAGUACCGCAAAAGCUGCAAGGAGAUUCUGAACAGGCUCCUGCACAGACGCUCCAUCCACUCCUCUGGCCUCACAGGCGACUCUCACAGCCAGAACAUUCUGCCGGUGUCUGAGUGAAGGACCGCGCUCCUGCUGAAGAGUUUAGAAUGAGGCAGCGGUGAGAAGAAGGGUGGGAGGGCGUGGGGGCCCCUGGGUGGACACCACCAGCCACCAGUCCCUGGCAUGCCCAGUGAUCCUGGUUCCCUGGCUUGUAGGGGCUCCAGAGCCUGCUUCCUGGUUCCUCAAGGGCAGAUAUUGGACACUCCUUAUUUGUCACCAAAGGAUGACUGUAGGCCGUGUGCUGGCCUUUCUUUCUAAGAAGCUGCUUUGAGCUCCUGGACUCACCUGAGGCUCCCUGGGGGAUGACACUCAGUUCUGUCACUGUCAAGGAUGCAGAGAGCUGGUGGUAGGUGGGAAGCAUGGUGUCCACCUGCCUGCUGACCACUGGACGCUGCUCCAUGCUGAAGAAAAGUGACAGUCUCCAGGGGACAUUUCAGCCAUGCUGAAAGGGAGGCUGGCAGUGGUCAUUUGGCCCGGAUCUAACAUGGCACCUCGUCUCCACAGGGUAGUGGUGGCUGCUUCAACCCAAAUAUUAUUCAGCUGGUACUAACGACAUUGUGCCCAGCUGGGACUCUUGGGCUCUGUGCCUGAGGGAAAAUGUUUCACAACUAGUGGCUGCCCAAUUGCUGCUGACCAGUUGUCUUAGAAAUGGUCAAUUGGAUUCAACUUUAGUCCUCUCCUUCCCCCUAAAAGCGAAUGUUUGUGUGUGCAGACAAUCUUAGCAUGAAAAUGGUUUAAAUAGGCUGGUCCUACAUGUAUUAGGUUCUUUCAAGUUUGACUGGGAGGUCACCUUUUUCUGAUUUACAAGUCCUAAUUGUUGGAGCUCAGUAAAGGUAGGAGGAAGGUGGCUGGUUGGUCCUCCCUUCCCCCUGUUUGUGACCUGAAUUUACAGGAAGUGUUUCAACUUGUCUUAUGCAUCUUAUCUGGCAUGUCCUGGGAGAUGGAUGGGCAAGAACUGGCCUGAGCAGGGAUUUUUGCCUUGAUUUUAAGUCACUGGGUUCCAUUGUCCUGGCACCUCCAUUUCCUUAGUUUCUGUAAGCCUGUUAACAGAAAGUAGAGGCUAUUCAAGGUUAUCAAGAAAGUGCCCUGUGCUAAUGAUGAGACAGUGAAUUUUUUUUUUUUUUCGAGAUGGGAGUUUCACUCUUAUUGCCCAGGCUAGAGUGCAAUGGUGCGAUCUAGGCUCACCACAACCUCUGCCUUCCAGGUUCAAGUGAUUAGAGACAGUGAAAUUUUUAUGGAAUACUGCACCUAUAAAACACAUGCCAAUCUGUUAGCAGUCCUGACUUGAUUUAAUAAAAACCAAGGAGAGCCACCCCUGCUUUCUGGCCAUCUCUUCUUUGUCUACCAUUUCAAAUUGACUUGUGAAUACUCAGAGCAGUUAUUUUUCAAUCCUCCACUCUAAGUGAUUCCUCCAGGGUGGGAAGCACGGGGAGCAAUGGAAUCAGAUGGCUCAUUCUCUCCUUCCAGCUCUUUACAUCCUAACUUUGGAGGUAUAGAAGGAAGGAUGUGGUCCAACGGGAAGGAAGUGAAGAGUCUAUUGGUUUUUACUUCUAGGCAGUCCCAAUUUUUAAAGGCAGAGAAGUAUCUGCAUCUUUAUUUGAAAAGACGUCUUAUUAACUCUUAGCUCCUCAGUUAGAAAACAAUUCACCUGGCUUAGUCUUGUCUAGUUUCAAAGUUACCAUGGAGACUAGAAUGGAGACAGGUGUAGCUUCCAAGGAGGCCUUGGCAUCUUGCAGUUGCUGUCAGAGAUGGGCUCAUAUCUGCUUGGGGAAGCCAAUGGGGCACAAUCCUUCCCAAUUUCAUGAUCUGGGGCAUCAUGUCGGUAGCUGAAGUCAGCCACGGUGGGAGUGUUUAUACCAUGAAAAUCAGCAAGUGCUGUAAAUCAGGCCUUUUGCCCCACAGAGAGCUGAUUGUGAAACAUCUACUAGCACACCACUGCCAGACAUGACUGUGUGUGUCCCUGAAACAAAAUUGCUCUGGCUCAGAGCUCCUUUGGCCACUCAUAUUACAAUAGCAACAGACAUUUGCUUCCUGGUGGCAAGUAACUGUGCACCCUCCAACAUCCCAACCCCAGAGGAACCAGUGGGAUUGAAAACCAGCAGAAGCCAAGACAGGAUGCACAGCUGAAUUGGAGGAGAGUAGCUCCCUUCUCACACAAACGCUUUCAAAGUUGGGCAAAAGUGGCCCAGUGCGUGAGGUCAGUCAACAGCCAAAUUCCAGCAGCAAAAUACAUUUUCAUCAAUAUCACUUUGGGAGAAUAACUGUGGCACAUGCUCUUUCUGCUUUCUCUGUACUGUAUAGGCAACAUGUUGUACUCCCAGUAGCAACUAGAUCUCUUUUACCUCUUCUUUAGCCAAGAAGCAAGAUCUGUCACCCACAACACCACAUAUCUUGAAAAGAUGCUUUUCAUAAUUUUCACUAUACCUCUAAAACCAAUUGUACCGACAUCACGUAGACAAAAACUCCAGAUAAAUCCAUUGAUUGGGUAUUUUCAUUAUUAUUUGGACACAUGAAUUAAAUCCCAAGGGAAAGUGAGAAGAAAAUUAAUGUAUUAGCAACCAGUGUUAGCCAACUCUGCUGUAAUUACCUUUAGAUAAAUGUUUAUUUUCAUCUCUAUACAGUCUAUCAAAUUUGCCCCCUGGCUUUAUUACUCCCAAUUGAAUUAUCUACCUCAUUUUGUUAAUUUAAUUUAUCAAAGGUAACAUUGUUUUCUCAGGUAUAACACAUAGAAACACCAAGAUUUUCAGCAUCUGAAUCAAACUAAAAUUACUUGCUUGACUUCACUCCAGGGUGAGACUUGACCUUUAAGGCCCAAACUCUGGUGAACUGUUGGACUGGGUAGAAAUCUUUCAAGAAGCUUGAAAAUAAGGCCAUAAAGGAGGGGCUUUCAAAUUCCUAAAUCCACAUAUAGGGCUGAGUUCCUAGUCCUACACAAUCAGAAUUUGCCUUUUUAAGUCACGCUGCAACUAUUCCGGCUUUUUAUAUGGCACCUUUCUGAGGGAGGGGAUUUUACAGCCGAGGGACCUCCAAAGGGAACGUCCAUUUGCAUGUGUGCCCUGGUAUUUAGGGUUUGUCUCAUGGUCAGCUCGCCUCUCAAAGAUGGCUCACCAAUCACCUGCCUGUUUUUACUUAGAAAGCAGGCUUGGGCAGGAGGGGAAAUGGAUUUGAACCAUCUCAGACCAACUCUAUCUCUUCUAGCACUCAGCUCAGCCUCCUGUCCCCAUGAGCAAUAAAACUCUCUCCUUAUGUCUGUGAAAUUCGUUUUCUUUUUCAUGGUGCCUUUCUUUCUAAGAAAAGAUAGAAAGAAUGGGGCCAGGUUCAUGUCCCAGUUGUCACCCUUUUACAUGCUUGGGUGCAGGUAGAUGAGGCCUUCCCAUGGCUACAGUGUGACCCUUGGAGGAACCAAAGGCUGUGCAUUGUUAGAAUUUAGCCCAGAUGCAGGAUAAACUAGCUUGCCUGAGUUUAAUGAGGAUAUUAUAUCAGGUGCCAGGAAUCCCUUGGGUCAGCUCCUAUCCUCUGGACGGGGAGCAUCAUGGGAAAAAGAGGUCCGAGUCAUAUUUAGGGCUUCAUGUGUCUGGAAGGGAGCCAUUAGCUCUUAAAUUAUUCACAGAAGUCACCACGGAAGGUUGUUUAAGAUGCAGAUUCCAGCAUCCCCUCCUCAGAGAUCAAUUUCAGCAGGGCCAGGCAGGACCUGGGUUUCCGCACUUUUAAUCAUCGAUGCCCAGGUAACUGAUAGGAGUUUUCUUCAAACCAUCCCCUAAGGAGAAAUGAUCUUAGACACUUGGAUAAACUCUAUAGAAAAUUGAGUGUUUCUAUUAAUAACUAUCUAGGUUUCAAUUGUCUUGUAUCUUUCCCUAAUUCUCCAAACAGUUCAAUCUCCAGCUUUAUUCAAUGGCUGGGCCAUUUUGUUCUUGGAGGGACAAAAUUGACCUCUCCAUGAAAUUGCAAAAACCCAUCUUCAUUCCUUUUUAUGGGGCUCCAGGUCAUAAGGAUGAGAUAUAUUUGGGGUACUGGCAGAGGAUGGCAGAGCUGGCUGGCUCUGAGCCAGGAAGCCUUGUUAGAGGAAGGAACUCUGGCAUUCAGAGGUGUCCCCUUGGGGGCACUUGCUUGGGUCUUGGAUCAAACUCUACUGGGGCAGCCUGGCUGUGGGAGGUGAUGACAUCUGCCACCUCUGCCACUACCCAGAGCUUGUCCUGCCCUCUUCCCAGCCAGCCUCACACACAGGAGCUGAGCCAGGCUGAGGCAAGGUCAGCGAGAGACAGUUCUCCAUGCCAGUAUCUGGGUGUGGGUCUCUUGUUGGCUCCCAGCUCAUCCCGUGUGGCUGACCCUUCCAGGUCACUUGGAGCAGCCAGUAAUGACAGUGUCCUAACAGCUGGUGGGUAUGGAGGAAAGACUAGACAUCAGGCUAUGGACUCACAUGGAGGGCCCUGGUGUUGGCUCUGGGACCUGGGCUGGGCCGGACCUGGGGAGAGGGUGGGUGGAGCUUGGCCUCUGCAGUUUGCGCUUGCAGGUUCAGGGGAGAAAGUUGUUUGAGAUCAGGGUUUAGGGGUAGUGUUUCCCAUUAAUCUUCAUCAUAAUCUUUUGAUGUAGGUGCUGUUAUUAUCUCUACGUUACACAUCUGGGAGGAUUUGAAAGUCCUGGAGACAGGGAGGUUUUGGGGAGAAUGCAAAACAGGGCAGGGCUCUCAAGGAGGGUGGACCAGUGACCAUGGGGAAACUGAGUGUUUCUAUUAAUAAGUAUCUAAGUUUCAAUUGUCUUGUAUCUUUCCCUAAUUCUCCAAACGGUUCAAUCUCCAGUUUUAUUCAGGGACUGGGCCAUUUUGUUCUCAGAGGGACAAAACUGAUCUCUCCAUGAAAUCCCCUGCACCUCACUCUGGGCAGCUCUAGGCUCAGCAGAUGUUUUUCUGCCAUUAGGAAACAGCCCCUUACUCUCAGCUCCUGUGCUAACACCCAUACCCACCAGCUGGGCGUUGGGACCUCUCCCGUCAUAUGGCUGCCACUUGCUUGGGAAGGAAUUCUCCAGACUCCUUUUACUUUGUAUGUGUUUCUAGGGGAAUUCUGAGGGAAGAAGCUUUGCAGCAACCUCUGUGCCCAGAACAUACGGCUCACAAGUCCUUUGUGCCGACAGGGAAUCUAUCUAAUUGUUUUAGUGUGUGAGGCUCAUUGUCAGCCUAGAUUUCCCUGAAACUCUGGGCCAGCAGCCCCCAGGAGCAUCAGUAGGACCCAGCAUUUCCCCUGGCACCAAAGUGGACCUCUUUGCACCUUGCAGCCGGGAGAACUGACUUAGAGGGCCCUGGUGUUGGCUCUGGAACCUGGGCUGAGAUGGAUUCGGGGAGAGGCUGGGUGGAGCUUGGCCUCUACGGUCUGUUCUUGCAGAUUCAGGAGAGAAAGUGGUAUGAGAGCAGUGUGGUUUGUAAGUUCCCCAACUUCCCCGCUGGCUCACACUGUCUCCCCAGACCAAUGGCCUAUUAGCCCCCAAAAAGUUAGUCCAACCCCAGGCCAGCUGCCUUUGCUCUGCUGUGGCCUAAGUUCUGGCCUGGUCAAAGGAAGGUGGCAGGAACUCCAGGCUUGCUCCUGCCUCCUCACACCUCAUUCCACAAAUGCGGAGUGAAAGAGCAGGAGCCAGACACAUUUGGGGGUUGACUGUCUAGAAAGGAGGAAUCAGAGGUCCCAAGGAACACAAUCGUGCAACUUCCUAGGGAAUCUGCAUCAGGAGAAAGAAGCGGCUAGGACACACAGUGGCUUCGCUCAGCCUGGCCACGACAUCACUGUGCAGAAGAAGAGAUCUGUCAGGGGUCCAGAGGAGCGGAGUCCUGGAGCCUCUGGGAGGGUGGCAUGUGGCAGCUGCAGGCUGUGGUCCAGAACUAUGAGCAGACUUGCCUGUCACUCUCCAAACAUUUACUGAACACCUACUGUGUGCCAGGCCCUGUGCUUUGUCAGGCUCUGGGGGAGACAGGUCAUUACUCUGCAGUGUGGGAAGCGGGGCUGCCCUGGAAGUGUGUACUCAGUGCUGUGGGGGUACAGAGGGAGGGCUGGAGAACUUAGCUGGUGGGAAAGGAGGGUUCUGGAAGGCUUCUCAGAGGUAGUGGCAUUGGGCCAGAACUUACAGUAGGGAAGAGCAUGUGGCAAGGCACAGAGGAGAUGGGAGCCUGCCUGGUGAGGGGUCCAGUGGUGACAGAGCUCAGUGUGGGUCCAGAGAUGGUGUCAGGUGAGGGCUGAGAGGGGAGGGCAAGUGCCCCUUGAGAUGGGCUGAACGUGAUGAUGAUCUGUGGCCAGUGGGAGAUGAUAGAAGUCUUGAGGUUGGGAAUAUAAGAAUUAGGUCUCUUUUAGAAAGAGAGGACAUGGAGAAAAUCCAUAUAUUUUUAGCUACCAAAAAAGAGAAGGAAGAAAGAAAAGAAAUAAGAAGAGAAGCAAGACAGAAAAGAAGGAAGAGAGAAGGAAGAAUGGCAAAGGAAGGAAGAAGGAGAGAAGGAAGGAAAAACAAAGGAAGGAGAAAAAGGGAAGGAAAGAAGAAAGGAAGGAAAAAAGGAAGGAGGGAGGGGAGGAAGGAAAAGAAAAAGAAGGAAGGAAGGAGUCCUAGCCACUUCUUUCUCCUGAUGCAGAUUCCCUAGGAAGUUGAACGAAGAAGGAAGGAAGGAAGAAAGGAGAGAAAGGAGGAAGGAAAAUGAAUCUCAUUCAUUUUGAGGGGCAUCUUCAUUACACAGCGUGGGGAGGGAAGCAUAAUUCACUCUUAAGAAACCAACCACACCAGCCAGGGCCCAUCUUCUGACAAUAUCCUGAAGGGUUCGAAUGUUUGUCUUCGGUAGGGAGUGCCACACAUUUAAUAUCAAUGCAGGGUCCUGAUGGGCACUGCCACAUACCCCCAGGACAAACGGAAAAAUCCACACAGCAGAAACAAGCAGUUGGCAAAAGCUGUCCUCAUGCUACUUGGCAAUUCAAUCACCCUCCCUUCACUCCCACACCUAUCUCCGGGUGUUGCCCGUACAGUGUGUCAUGUAAAUAGCAUCUAGCAUUUAAAGGUCAAAUUUGAUGAGUCUAAUCAAUCUUAGCAGUGUUCCAGUUCAUCACGUAUACCCAUAUUUAAGGACUUUUAAAGUAAUUUGGAUUUUUAACUCAAAAGACGAUGUGUACCCCUUGGGGCAUGCGUGUGUUCUUAGGAACACCAGCGUGUGGUAUUUCCUGUGUCCUCUCAUGCAUGCUCAGCAUGUCACUGUUGUACUCAUUCCCUGGCACGGAAGAAUUGUUGCACAUCUUUAAUAGAAGCCAAAGCCCAUGAUUUGAUGGUUUCAAGAGCCUAAAAUCUGUAUUUGGAGAGAGGAAGUCUACUCUUAACUGUGAGAGUUAAGAGUAUCACCAUCAAGGCGCAAGGCUUCAGUCUUAUCCCGGACAAUCCUCAGGGAUUGGGUUUGAUGUCGGGGGAGCAUUGGAUGCCAUCACGUUGACACUCAAUUGAUUGGGUGACCCAAGAUGGUCAGUUUCCUAAGGACCAGACCAUAGUGACUGCUCAUGCAUCGGCUGAAAUACCAAACACCCUGCACCAAAAGACUCAGCUUGACAUUGCUUUGCACUCAACUCAUGUAUUACCAAAUCUUUGCUUGAAUUAUUAAUAGUAACCAAACUCUCUGCUCUAACAACCUUCGAAUGUCAAGUUCCCUUGCAAGCUGAAAUUGUUCCAAACCUCAACACUCCUGUUUUACAACAAACAUGUAAAUACAACCUCUUUUGGAGUGCAGAAACAUUUGCGGAGUCUGGUGUGCCACCAACCCCAUCAGGAUUUCCCCAGGGGAAAAUGGCUAACUCUGGAUCACAAACAGCACAAAUUAAAAAGGUGCCUUGCCUGAUGCCCAUUACCACCUGGGGUGGUUUUUCUAGACACCAGAAUAGGCCAGAUUUAAUUUUCACAGGCUCAUCUGGGAGAAGGAUCAAAUCCUGCCAUCUGGAUGUGCAUUAUUAAUGCUGGUGUUUGGUGAGGAAGCUCCUAGGAAUGCAUAGAUCUCUCCUUCUGCCAUAGUAUGUCGUGUGUAGUGGAUGCCAGUAGACAACUUUAGCCACUCCUGUCCGUCCUUCUUCAUGGAACACACUCAUUUCGCCACACGGAGGCUUUACUCUGCCCAGUGUCCAAUGGGAGAACCAUCCCUUCCCUUUAGUGAGAGGACAGCUGGCUAAAUGCUAUCCUCAGUCCUCCUGGAGGCUCCUAGUAAUGAGGGCACUGAACACCAAUUCUUUACAUUCCUUGAAUUUUCAUAGAUUCUAUUUUUUUCAUGUCUGUGAAAAGUGGGGUGGGGAACUCACACCAACCAUAGCUUGGGGCAUCCAGAGAGUGGCUAGUAGAUGAUAGAAGGGAGUCCAGUUAAGGAAACCUAAGGUAUGUGCCAGCUGGUUUAGCAUUCAAUAUGGAAAUGCACUUUAUAUUUAUUUGCACACAUCAAGAAUACUUUUGGAAACCAGGAUUUAGAAAAAUAAAAGAUAUUUCUUUCCUGGGGACAAAGUGACCUGCAAAUGAUUGGCUUCUGUACAAUGUUGCAAUCCCUUAAUGUCAGACUCUUAGGAAAAUGGGUGGGACAUCUGUGUGUUUGUGUUGGAGUGAAUGUGCCCAUAACCCUGUGCUCCCAUAAGUCUGUGUGCCCGUGAUCAUAUGCAUAUGGGUGAAUGUUUGUGUGCCCAUGAUUUUAUGCAUAUAGGUGAAUAUUUGUGUGCCCAUGAGCAUAUGCAUAUGGGUGAAUGUUUGUGUGCCCAUGAGUAUAUGCAUACGGGUGAAUGUUUGUGUGCCCAUGAGUAUAUGCAUAUGGGUAUAUGUUUGUGUGCCCGUGAUUAUAUGCAUAUGGGUGAAUGUUUGUGUGCCCGUGAUUAUAUGCAUGUGGGUGAAUGUUCAUGAACACAAACAGCUACACUCGGAGUAGAAAACAAAUGAAGCAAAAGUUUAGCAUCCUCUCAUGUGUGUCAACAUUGUAGUUUUACAUUUACUUUCUUCUAAUCUAUUAAACAUAAGUAUGGCUCCAUUUUUUUAGUAUUACCAGAAGCCCUCCCAAUACGGCAAUAUUACCUUCUGUGUAAUCCACUUGCCAACAGCUGUUUUCUGUUGAAAUGGGACUCAAGAAUUUUGAAUCCAAGGCCAAUGCUGCCUGCUCUGUUUACAAUGGUUUGUGUUUUGUGGAUACAUAUCAAAUGCUGUAAUAUAUUUUUAUGAUAGAAUUGAUGGUUAAUACAGGGAAAAAGUAUAUAUUGUGAUUCUGUCCAAUAAAGCCUCCUGUUAUAAAA